GGUGCACGCUGAAGGAGCCGGCGGAACCGGGUGGCCAUGGGGAUGUGGGCAUCGCUGGACGCUUUGUGGGAGAUGCCGGCCGAGAAGCGUAUCUUCGGGGCCGUGCUGCUCUUUUCCUGGACAGUGUAUCUUUGGGAGACCUUCCUAGCACAGCGGCAGAGAAGGAUAUAUAAAACAACAACUCAUGUACCACCGGAGUUAGGACAGAUCAUGGAUUCUGAAACAUUUGAGAAAUCUCGACUCUAUCAACUGGAUAAAAGCACUUUCAGCUUCUGGUCAGGACUCUAUUCAGAGACUGAAGGCACUCUUAUUCUUCUCUUUGGAGGAAUACCUUAUCUCUGGAGACUUUCUGGACGGUUCUGUGGUUAUGCUGGCUUUGGACCAGAAUAUGAGAUCACUCAGUCCCUGGUGUUUCUGCUGUUGGCUACACUUUUCAGUGCAUUGACUGGUUUGCCAUGGAGUCUUUAUAAUACUUUUGUGAUAGAAGAAAAACAUGGCUUCAAUCAACAGACUUUGGGGUUCUUCAUGAAAGAUGCAAUCAAGAAAUUUGUUGUGACUCAGUGUAUUUUGUUGCCUGUGUCUUCACUUCUACUUUACAUUAUUAAAAUUGGGGGUGACUAUUUUUUUAUUUAUGCCUGGCUGUUCACAUUAGUUGUGUCUCUGGUUCUUGUCACAAUCUAUGCUGAUUAUAUUGCCCCUUUAUUUGACAAAUUCACACCUCUGCCUGAGGGAAAGCUUAAAGAAGAAAUUGAAGUAAUGGCAAAGAGUAUUGACUUUCCUUUGACGAAGGUGUAUGUUGUGGAAGGAUCUAAACGCUCUUCCCACAGCAAUGCUUAUUUUUAUGGCUUCUUCAAGAACAAGCGAAUAGUUUUGUUUGACACUCUACUAGAAGAGUACUCUGUACUAAACAAAGACAUCCAGGAGGAUUCUGGCAUGGAACCCCGCAAUGAGGAAGAAGGGAACAGUGAAGAAAUAAAAGCUAAAGUUAAAAAUAAGAAACAAGGAUGUAAAAAUGAGGAGGUACUCGCUGUACUAGGCCAUGAACUGGGGCACUGGAAGUUGGGACAUACAGUCAAAAAUAUCAUUAUUAGCCAGAUGAAUUCUUUCCUGUGUUUUUUUUUAUUUGCUGUAUUAAUUGGUCGAAAGGAGCUUUUUGCUGCAUUUGGUUUUUAUGAUAGCCAACCCACUCUUAUUGGACUAUUGAUCAUCUUCCAGUUUAUUUUUUCACCUUACAAUGAGGUUCUUUCUUUUUGCCUAACAGUCCUAAGCCGCAGAUUUGAGUUUCAAGCUGAUGCAUUUGCCAAGAAACUUGGGAAGGCUAAAGACUUAUAUUCUGCUUUAAUCAAACUUAACAAAGAUAACUUGGGAUUCCCUGUUUCUGACUGGUUGUUCUCAAUGUGGCAUUAUUCUCAUCCUCCACUGCUAGAGAGACUUCAAGCUUUGAAAACUAUGAAGCAACACUGAGAUGUCCAGGAUCUGUGACUGAAGACAUUUCUGAUUAUUUCUGUCCUGGCAGCAUGUUCCAGCUCUUGAUGUUUUUAAACUUUUUUUUAGAAGAAAAAUUAAGUACAGAAAAGCCCAGAUUUAAAUACAUUUAAUAUGUCAUUUUAAAAAUGAUUUUAAUAAUUCAUUUCUUAAAACACUGAAUGAAUUUUGAAGCUUAAUGUUUUUAAAGGCAUAGUUUUAUCUUUGACAUCUAAUUUACCAUCAAGUUGUAAAAUUAUUUGGAAAAAUACAGAACUCGUUUUAUUUGUAUACUUAUAUGGAAUCUGCAUGUGAGGUGUUUGAGGGCAUAUGUUUGAAAGAGGGAGCAUCACCACAGGAAUCCUUUCUGUGAGGUGGAAACAGUGGUCCUGAAUCAUUGUGCUCACACCUAACUUGAAAUCUGGUCUUACUUUCAUGCUGUUAUGAUUUCACCUGGUGAAUCAGUGUUUUAAAUAAGAAAGGUAAUAGUUGGUAAGGCCAAUGUUAUUUAAAUGAAAGUAGUUAGAAAAAUGCUCUCCUAUUCUACCAAAUUUUUAAUUUCUUUCUUCCCUUUCUUGCUACACAGUGAUCAAGAGUUUCUCAUAGUGCUUUGAAGUUAGAAAUUAUGUAUAGGAUAUUUUAAAUCAUUGAGUUUUGUGGGGUUUUUUUGUUUGUUUGUUUCUUUUGUUUUUUGGAAAAUCCGUGUCUUUAUCUUUUUUUCCCACGUGGUAGAUAUGAUCCCAUUGGAGGUAAAUUGUAGCUUCUUCUCAUUCAUGCAGUAAAUAAUACAUCCUUUCACUCAGCAGAGAUGGCCAUAUUAAACACGUUUUGCUAUGUUAAAAGUGGCAGAACAGGAAAGACGAAUUAAAAAUAACAUUUUUUAAGCGACAUAAGGAUGAAAUACUGAUGAAUCUCUGUGACAUUACAGGGAAAAAAAUAUAGUUUUCUAUCUCUUUCAAGGGCAGAAGAGUUUUCAUUUUUAUUUUUGUAAUUUUAUCUGUAAGUCAUAAAUAUUACUUAAUCAGGCCUGAUUCUACUUUUGAAAAUUACAGUUCUUGAAAUGCAGAUAAUGUUUACUUUGAAAACAAAUGUCAUGAAUGAUUUCCAGUUUUUAAAGCUAUAUGUUUCACUGCUUCAUAUCUCUGUCCACUUUCUGAAUGAGAACUUAUUUUGUGCCUAGAGCUCUCACUCACUGAUAAUGCUUAUUACCUUCUGGGCAUUUAUUCCAAAGUGGGAUCAACUGUACGCCUUUGGUAUCUGACCAUAAAGUCUUUUGCUCCGCUGACAUUUGGGUGAUGUCUUCACAUGGAAAUAUAAUAAAAAUAAAAAUCUAGUUUAAUACUGCAUUAUUUAUUUUCCUAAGGCUAAAGAGGAGCAGUCCUAUGCUUUUAUUCAGCAUCCUUUAUCUGUGACUUCAUGCUCUGAUAACUGCCUUUCCUUCCUUCUGUGCCUUUGAAUACAAAUUUCAGUUCUGCAAAAGUGAAACAUUAAACAUUGCCAACGCAAAUGUA